GAAGAGAAAGGCAGAGAGAGUCGGGUUACAAGAUGGCGGAUCUGUAGUAGUUACCGCGGCGGCGGGAGAGCAAGCGAGCCCUGGGGGGCAAAGAGACGGGAGAGUGGGUGUAUGCGCGGGUGAAGUGAGAGGUAACGGGGCCUCCGGGCGGAGAGGCCUCAGUGGCUCUUGUCACCCCUUCUCGCGGCUGAACCUUUGGAGCCAUGGUGAAUUCGGGCCUCUCCGAAGCCGCCGCCGCCGCCACCGCCACUACUGCCUUUACCGUCUCCUAAGAGUGAGGAGCGCGGACGAGGUAAGCGAGGAGGCGGCGGCUAGAGCGGUGGAGACAGCAGCCACCAUGUCGGAUACGCGGCGGCGAGUGAAGGUCUAUACCCUGAACGAAGACCGGCAAUGGGACGACCGAGGCACCGGGCACGUCUCCUCCACUUACGUGGAGGAGCUCAAGGGGAUGUCGCUGCUGGUUCGGGCAGAGUCCGACGGAUCACUACUCUUGGAAUCAAAGAUAAAUCCAAAUACUGCAUAUCAGAAACAACAGGAUACAUUAAUUGUUUGGUCAGAAGCAGAGAACUAUGAUUUGGCUCUGAGUUUUCAGGAGAAAGCUGGCUGUGAUGAGAUCUGGGAAAAAAUUUGUCAGGUUCAAGGUAAAGACCCAUCAGUGGAAGUCACACAGGACCUCAUUGAUGAAUCUGAAGAAGAACGAUUUGAAGAAAUGCCUGAAACUAGUCAUCUGAUUGACCUGCCCACAUGUGAACUCAAUAAACUUGAAGAGAUUGCUGACUUAGUUACCUCAGUGCUCUCCUCACCUAUCCGUAGGGAAAAGCUGGCUCUCGCCUUGGAAAAUGAAGGCUAUAUUAAAAAACUAUUGCAGCUGUUCCAAGCUUGCGAGAACCUAGAAAACACUGAAGGCUUACACCAUUUGUAUGAAAUUAUUAGAGGAAUCUUAUUCCUAAAUAAGGCAACUCUUUUUGAGGUAAUGUUUUCUGAUGAGUGUAUCAUGGAUGUCGUGGGAUGCCUUGAAUAUGACCCUGCUUUGGCUCAGCCAAAAAGACAUAGAGAAUUCUUGACCAAAACUGCAAAGUUCAAGGAAGUUAUACCAAUAACAGACUCUGAACUAAGGCAAAAAAUACAUCAGACUUACAGGGUACAGUACAUUCAGGACAUCAUUUUGCCCACACCAUCUGUUUUUGAAGAGAAUUUUCUUUCUACUCUUACGUCUUUUAUUUUCUUCAACAAAGUUGAGAUAGUCAGCAUGUUGCAGGAAGAUGAGAAGUUUUUGUCUGAAGUUUUUGCACAAUUAACAGAUGAGGCUACAGAUGAUGAUAAACGGCGUGAAUUGGUUAAUUUUUUCAAGGAGUUUUGUGCAUUUUCUCAGACAUUACAACCUCAAAACAGGGAUGCAUUUUUCAAAACAUUGGCAAAAUUGGGAAUUCUUCCUGCUCUUGAAAUUGUAAUGGGCAUGGAUGAUUUGCAAGUCAGAUCAGCUGCUACAGAUAUAUUUUCUUAUCUAGUAGAAUUUAGUCCAUCUAUGGUCCGAGAGUUUGUAAUGCAAGAAGCUCAGCAGAGUGAUGACGAUAUUCUUCUUAUUAAUGUGGUAAUUGAACAAAUGAUCUGUGAUACUGAUCCUGAGCUAGGAGGCGCUGUUCAGUUAAUGGGACUUCUUCGUACUCUAAUUGAUCCAGAGAACAUGCUGGCUACAACUAAUAAAACCGAAAAAAGUGAAUUUCUAAAUUUUUUCUACAACCAUUGUAUGCAUGUUCUCACAGCACCACUUUUGACCAAUACUUCAGAAGACAAAUGUGAAAAGGAUUUUUUUUUAAAACAUUACAGAUAUAGUUGGAGUUUCAUAUGUACCCCUUCACAUUCCCAUUCCCAUUCUACCCCCUCUUCCUCCAUCUCUCAAGAUAAUAUAGUUGGAUCAAACAAAAACAACACAAUUUGUCCCGAUAAUUAUCAAACAGCACAGCUACUUGCCUUAAUUUUAGAGUUACUCACAUUUUGUGUGGAACAUCACACAUAUCACAUAAAAAACUAUAUUAUGAACAAGGACUUGCUAAGAAGAGUCUUGGUCUUGAUGAAUUCAAAGCACACUUUUCUGGCCUUGUGUGCCCUUCGCUUUAUGAGGCGGAUAAUUGGACUUAAAGAUGAAUUUUAUAAUCGUUACAUCACCAAGGGAAAUCUUUUUGAGCCAGUUAUAAAUGCACUUCUGGAUAAUGGAACUCGGUAUAAUCUGUUGAAUUCAGCUGUUAUUGAGUUGUUUGAAUUUAUAAGAGUGGAAGAUAUCAAGUCUCUUACUGCCCAUAUAGUUGAAAACUUUUAUAAAGCACUUGAAUCGAUUGAAUAUGUUCAGACAUUCAAAGGAUUGAAGACUAAAUAUGAGCAAGAAAAAGACAGACAAAAUCAGAAACUGAACAGUGUACCAUCUAUAUUGCGUAGUAACAGAUUUCGCAGAGAUGCAAAAGCCUUGGAAGAGGAUGAAGAAAUGUGGUUUAAUGAAGAUGAAGAAGAGGAAGGAAAAGCAGUUGUGGCACCAGUGGAAAAACCUAAGCCAGAAGAUGAUUUUCCAGAUAAUUAUGAAAAGUUUAUGGAGACUAAAAAAGCAAAAGAAAGUGAAGACAAGGAAAACCUUCCCAAAAGGACAUCUCCUGGUGGCUUCAAAUUUACUUUCUCCCACUCUGCCAGUGCUGCUAAUGGAACAAACAGUAAAUCUGUAGUGGCUCAGAUACCACCAGCAACUUCUAAUGGAUCCUCUUCCAAAACCACAAACUUGCCUACGUCAGUAACAGCCACCAAGGGAAGUUUGGUUGGCUUAGUGGAUUAUCCAGAUGAUGAAGAGGAAGAUGAAGAAGAAGAAUCGUCCCCCAGGAAAAGACCUCGUCUUGGCUCAUAAAAUAUUUAUUAGGGGACCCUCAACAUGUGGUCUUACAAUGCUGCAACUGUUCAGUGAGCUGAAAAUCUGAAUCAGAAAGCUUUCUCAAUUGAACUUAUAAAAUAUACAAGGAGUAGCAAAAGACAGUAUAUCAGCUAAGAGAGUUUAGUUCUAAUAAAAAUCAGGCUUCCCAGGAACUUGAUUGCUUGCUAGUAAUUAAGGGGUUUGCCUUUUAGGCUGUCAAAACAAACAUUAGUAACCAGAACCUGGGAGACAGCUUCUCAGCAAGGAAAAGUCACAGGUUUGGGGACGGUUUAGGGGAGGGGAAAAGGUUGAUAUAAUAAUGCAGGGUUGCUCCUCGGGGUGUCGAUCUAGAAACAAUUUUACAGAACUUCAGUUGUAAACUCAAUAACAUUACUUGUAUAAUGGUGCUGGCCAUGUUGUUGUUUUAAUCAGUUGCCUCUUUUUAAAAGAAAUUUUUAUGGAAAACACAUUCAACUAUCAUUAAAAAAAUGAAGUUAAGCUGUUGGGACCAUUUCUUUAAGAUUUAACAAAAGUUCAGCCUUUUAGGUAGUUGAAGGGAAGUACACCCCGUAUUCAGCACAUGUUGAGUUUUCUACACCAGGAAUUUUCAAUAUGUAUAUUGAUGAAAACAAGCUCAAUUCAAACUGGACAGUUUUAAGAUAAUGUUAAAAUCAGCACUUUUAGAGACAACGAAGGCCAAGAAUCAGUACAGUAGUAUUCCAAAAUGAUUUUCUCUAGAAAUUUGAAAGUAGAUCGAACAGAAUGUUGUCAACCGCCUACCAGUACAAUCUUUUGUGGAAGAUACUUUGAAAUCACUUUCUACUUUGUUAGUAAAGUUCUGUCUUUCCAGAGCUGCAAGUUUUAAAGUGUUACUUAUACAGACCAACCAAGAAUAGUGCUGAAUUAAGUGGCAUUUAGUAUCUAGAAGCCAUUUUGAUCCAAGAAGCUACUUAAGUGUCAAAGUCAGCAUGCAGCACAUGUAGCUUUUCUGUAAACAAGGGUGUGAUAUGAAAGCUGCUUUUUUAAGAAGAGUAAAAGCACAUUCCAUAUACGUAAGUGAAUUUUAAAAAUAAAUUGAGGCAAACAGUUAAGUUUUAUUUUUAGAGCAACAAGUUAACUGUAAAUAUUUUAAUGUUAGUUUGCUCAUCUAUGAUCUGAGAUCAUGCCGAAGUGAGAAAAAUCUCCCCAAAAUACAAUUUAAUGCAUUGGGAAAAAAAAACUUUAACAGUAAUUCCAGCCACAAUCUUUAGAUCACCCUUGUAAUGUGUUACGGGUCCAUUUUUCCUGGAAUCGUUUAAUCUAAAGCAGUUUCCCCUGUUUUGGAGAUUUUGUAGUUAAUUUUAAUUUUGGCUAUUGUUUGGAAAAGAUGAGCUGUCUGUGUAGAUAUGAAGUAUAGUUUUUUCCAUAAAACAGAUGUUUAUUUUGUAUUAAAAAAUACCACUGUACUUGUUUUACACCAUUUGUAUACAUGUGGUGAUAUUAAUGCUAAACUGUAAAAUUCAGGAAUUAAAAUGUGACCCUGUAAUUCCAUAAUUGAUGUUUGUGUUUGGUUUGUUGUAAAUAUAAAUUAACUCCAUUUUGAGAUAUGUCAAUUUUACAGUAUCUUUUAAAAGCCAAUAAAAUUAUCCAUAAAUAUUUAUUAUAAACUGCUAGAUCAUACCCCAAUUUUAAUGAAAUAAUUCUAAACAAAUGCGGGUCAAUGGCACUUUAUCAGUGACUACUUAUAGAAGGUAAGCCUUGGGGAAAUCAUAGCAUCACAGUAUGGAGCUUUUCUCACCUUUUCAAUUAAAGGUGUACAUAUAGUAAGAAAGAAAGACCUUCCACCUCAUAAGGCAGGUGACUCAGGAUAUUUUAAACUAAGAUCAGUAAAGUUCCCAUCCACUUUCUUUGAAUCAUCAAAUUUUAUCGAGACCCAUCUCUCAGCUUUUAGUAAAUUUCUUCUUAAAAUAAGCCCACAUGUAAAACACUUUCCUAGUUACUUUUUGUUUGUUUGUUUGAGUCUCGCUCUGUUGCCCAGGCUGGAGUGUAGUUGCACGAUUUCGGCUUAUUGCAACAUCCGCCACCUGGGUUCAAGCAAUUCUCUGCCUCAGCCUGAGUAGCUGGGAUUACAGGUGCCCGUCACCAUGCCAGGCUAAUUUUUGUAUUUUCAGUAGAGACGGGGUUUCACCAUCUUGGCCAGGCUGGUCUUAAACUCCUGACCUCACAAUCCACCCGCCUCAGCCUCCCUAUCUCUGUAUCUUAUGAAGACUUCCUUUUUCUUUCUGAAGAGCUGCCAUAAGUCUUAAACAUUUAAAUCAUCAGAACCUUUUCUUGUAGCAGAAAUGUGAAUGUUUUCUUGAAGUACAGGUUACGGUUUUCAUGGUACAAGUGCUUACCUACGACGAUAAGAGAACAAGGCUUAAAAUAUCCCUCAAAAGAACAAUUGUGAGAAUUCCAUGUUAGCGGCUGUCUUUAAACGACUACCCUCAGGCAGAUCUGGGUUUUUAUAUCUUUAUCUUCAUUCAGUGAAGCAAGCCAAAAGCCCACAUUUGUAUGCCUUAGGUCUUCUUAAAAUGGUAUCUGUAAACAUGUGUCCAAUAUAAAAACUAUUUUUAAUAAAAAGUUACAUGAAACAGA